AGUGUUGGGGUUGCAGGAGACCUAAACACAGUCACCAUGAAGCUGGGCUGUGUCCUCAUGGCCUGGGCCCUCUACCUUUCCCUUGGUGUGCUCUGGGUGGCCCAGAUGCUACUGGCAGCUGGAUGUCAUGCCGCUGCCAGUUUUGAGACGCUGCAGUGUGAGGGACCUGUCUGCACUGAGGAGAGCAGCUGCCACACGGAGGAUGACUUGACUGAUGCAAGGGAAGCUGGCUUCCAGGUCAAGGCCUACACUUUCAGUGAACCCUUCCACCUGAUUGUGUCCUAUGACUGGCUGAUCCUCCAAGGUCCAGCCAAGCCAGUUUUUGAAGGGGACCUGCUGGUUCUGCGCUGCCAGGCCUGGCAAGACUGGCCACUGACUCAGGUGACCUUCUACCGAGAUGGCUCAGCUCUGGGUCCCCCCGGGCCUAACAGGGAAUUCUCCAUCACCGUGGUACAAAAGGCAGACAGCGGGCACUACCACUGCAGUGGCAUCUUCCAGAGCCCUGGUCCUGGGAUCCCAGAAACAGCAUCUGUUGUGGCUAUCACAGUCCAAGAACUGUUUCCAGCGCCAAUUCUCAGAGCUGUACCCUCAGCUGAACCCCAAGCAGGAAGCCCCAUGACCCUGAGUUGUCAGACAAAGUUGCCCCUGCAGAGGUCAGCUGCCCGCCUCCUCUUCUCCUUCUACAAGGAUGGAAGGAUAGUGCAAAGCAGGGGGCUCUCCUCAGAAUUCCAGAUCCCCACAGCUUCAGAAGAUCACUCCGGGUCAUACUGGUGUGAGGCAGCCACUGAGGACAACCAAGUUUGGAAACAGAGCCCCCAGCUAGAGAUCAGAGUGCAGGGUGCUUCCAGCUCUGCUGCACCUCCCACAUUGAAUCCAGCUCCUCAGAAAUCAGCUGCUCCAGGAACUGCUCCUGAGGAGGCCCCUGGGCCUCUGCCUCCGCCGCCAACCCCAUCUUCUGAGGAUCCAGGCUUUUCUUCUCCUCUGGGGAUGCCAGAUCCUCAUCUGUAUCACCAGAUGGGCCUUCUUCUCAAACACAUGCAGGAUGUGAGAGUCCUCCUCGGUCACCUGCUCAUGGAGUUGAGGGAAUUAUCUGGCCACCGGAAGCCUGGGACCACAAAGGCUACUGCUGAAUAGAAGUAAACAGUUCAUCCAUGAUCUCACUUAACCACCCCAAUAAAUCUGAUUCUUUAUUUUCUCUUCCUGUCCUGCACAUAUGCAUAAGUACUUUUACAAGUUGUCCCAGUGUUUUGUUAGAAUAAUGUAGUUAGGUGAGUGUAAAUAAAUUUAUAUAAAGUGAGAAUUAGAGUUUAGCUAUAAUUGUGUAUUCUCUCUUAACACAACAGAAUUCUGCUGUCUAGAUCAGGAAUUUCUAUCUGUUAUAUCGACCAGAAUGUUGUGAUUUAAAGAGAACUAAUGGAAGUGGAUUGAAUACAGCAGUCUCAACUGGGGGCAAUUUUGCCCCCCAGAGGACAUUGGGCAAUGUUUGGAGACAUUUUGGUCAUUAUACUUGGGGGGUUGGGGGAUGGUGGGAUGUGUGUGCUACUGGCAUCCAGUAAAUAGAAGCCAGGGGUGCCGCUAAACAUCCUAUAAUGCACAGGGCAGUACCCCACAACGAAAAAUAAUCUGGCCCAAAAUGUCAGUUGUACUGAGUUUGAGAAACCCCAGCCUAAUGAAACCCUAGGUGUUGGGCUCUGGAAUGGGACUUUGUCCCUUCUAAUUAUUAUCUCUUUCCAGCCUCAUUCAGCUAUUCUUACUGACAUACCAGUCUUUAGCUGGUGCUAUGGUCUGUUCUUUAGUUCUAGUUUGUAUCCCCUCAAAAGCCAUUAUGUUGAAAUCCUAAUCCCCAAGGUGAUGGCAUUAAGAAGUGGGCCUUUGGGAAGUGAUUAGAUCAGGAGUGCAGAGCCCUCAUGAUUAGGAUUAGUGCCCUUAUUUAAAAAGGCCCCAGAGAGCUAACUCACCCUUCCACCAUAUGAGGACGUGGCAAGAAGAUGACAUGUAUGAGAACCAAAAAACAGCUGUCGCCAAACACCGACUCUGUCGUUGCCUUGAUCUUGAACUUCCAGCCUCCAGAACUAUGAGAAAUAAAAUUCUGUUGUUUGUAAGCUA